GUCCCGGCAAAGGCUCGAGCGAAUUCGGACACGGGGCCCGGUCGCUCCGCCCGCGUCCCUGAGCCCGGCUCCCGCCCCGGCCCGCGCUCACCGCCGAUGAUGGUCCGGAUGAGGGAGGCGUGCCCGGGGCAGUCGACCAGCGUGACCUGAAGCAGUGGCUCGCCGGGCUCGGGCUCGGCCUCGGGCGCUGCCUGGAACUCGGGCAAAGACGACCGCAGGCGCGCGGGCAGCGGCACCGAGAAGCACGAGAAGCCCAGAUCGAGCGUGAUGCCGCGCUCGCGGCUCUGCGGCUGCUUGUCAAAGGCGGCGGUGGAGGCUGUGGUGCUUAGCGCCCGCGCCAGCGCCGUCUUGCCGCUGUCGAUGUGGCCCAGCACGCCCACGUUCACGUUCACCCGCCGCCCUGCCAUGCCGCCGCCGCCGCCUCGGACACCCGCCCGGCCCGCCCCUCACCUCCCUCGGUAGUCGCCGCGGUCCGGCCCGUUAAGUUGCCCCCCCGUAACCGGCGCGCUGUGCACACCCGUUCCGGCCCGGAAGCUUCCGCCCUCCUGAGGCUCACGGGCACAGCCGAGCGCCGUGCUCCGACUGGGUGGUCUAGGAACUGGAGGUCACCGUAGGCAGGGUUUCUCUCUCACGUGGCUCCUCCUGCCUGAAGCCUCUAGGAGCCCGAGAUGGAGGGAUCCUUCUGAGAAGUGAAGCCAUUUGGACUUUCUGGGUGAGUGGAGACUUGGAGAACUUUUCUAUAGCUAUCAAGAGGAU